AUUGCCUGUUUAAUAGUUGCUGUUGCUGCACUUCCGCUUCUCUCCCAGCGAGAGAGAGACACGAGUGGCCAGGCCCAGCCGCAGCCGCAGCAGCAGCCGCCGCGGCGGCACGGAGGAGCCAGACACAAAGAGAGGGGCUGUUUGCGGGGUGGGGUGGGGGGUUCGCUAUGUCGGAUGACGAUUCGAGGGCCAGCACCAGCUCCUCCUCAUCUUCGUCUUCCAACCAGCAAACCGAGAAAGAAACAAACACCCCCAAGAAGAAGGAGAGUAAAGUCAGCAUGAGCAAAAACUCCAAACUCCUCUCCACCAGCGCCAAGAGAAUUCAGAAGGAGCUGGCGGACAUCACUUUAGACCCUCCACCUAAUUGCAGUGCUGGUCCCAAAGGCGAUAACAUCUAUGAAUGGAGAUCAACCAUUCUAGGGCCUCCAGGAUCCGUGUAUGAGGGUGGUGUAUUCUUUCUCGAUAUCACUUUUACACCAGAAUAUCCCUUCAAGCCUCCAAAGGUUACAUUUCGGACAAGAAUCUAUCAUUGUAAUAUUAACAGUCAAGGUGUUAUUUGCUUGGACAUAUUGAAAGAUAAUUGGAGUCCAGCACUAACCAUUUCUAAAGUCCUCCUUUCUAUCUGCUCACUUCUUACAGACUGUAAUCCUGCCGACCCCUUGGUGGGAAGUAUUGCCACUCAGUAUAUGACCAACAGAGCAGAACAUGACAGAAUGGCCAGACAGUGGACCAAGAGAUACGCUACAUAAAUUGGGGUUUCACAAUUCUUACAUUAUUUGUCUGUCACAGAAGAGAGCUGCUUAUGAUUUUGAAGGGGUCAGGGAGGGUGGGAGUUGGUAAAGAGUAGGGUAUUUCUAUAACAGAUAUUAUUCAGUCUUAUUUCCUAAGAUUUUGUUGUAACUUAAGGUAUCUUGCUACAGUAGACAGAAUUGGUAAUAGCAACUUUUAAAAUUGUCAUUAGUUCUGCAAUAUUAGCUGAAAUGUAGUACAGAAAAGAAUGUACAUUUAGACAUUUGGGUUCAGUUGCUUGUAGUCUGUAAAUUUAAAACAGCUUAAUUUGGUACAGGUUACACAUAUGGCCAUUUAUGUAAAGUCCCUCUAAGACUACAUACUUUUUGUUUAAAACAAAAUUGGAAUUUGUUUUCCCUUCUUGGAAGGGAACAUUGAUAUUUAACAGAGUUUUUAGAGAUUGUCAUCUCAUAUAUAUAAAAUGGACACGUGGCUAUAAAACACCAUAUAAGAGAUGAGUAGUGCGUUUUAUUUUAUAUGCCAAUCUACUUUGUUUAAAAAAGGUCUGAAUCAGGACUUGUGAAAACCUGUAGUGAAAUACCUUAAGCUGUUAACUAACUGUAAGGCGUGGAAUAGGAGUUGCUCAGUGGAUUGGUUCUAUGUUGUGGACUACUUAAGUCUGCAUUUGUUACUGUGCUAAUAAACAAUAUUAAAAACCACCUAAUAAACACUGCUGUGUUCAUUUACUUUUCUUUUGCCUUUUGGUUGCCAUUCGCAGAUUCUUCUGAAAUCGAUAGGUAUCUGCUUCUAAAACAAGCUAAAAAUAAUGCAUAUUUAGUAGGUAUUAGUUAGUUACCUAUAUUAGGAUCUGUACUUUACACAGCUGUAGAUGAGGUAUCCUAGAAAAGGUUAAAUAAUCUACCCCAUUUAGGCUUCAAAGACGAACCCUACUGCAUCUUUUUAAAAGCAUUUUCUGACUUGCAGAUGCUGUAGUAGCAAGUACAUGAGAAAUGGGUUCCGUCAUGGAUAAAUUGGUACCCUGCCUUAGGGGGCA